GGAGGGACCAGAAACCCCAGGGCGGGGGGGCGGCGGGGGCGGGGGUGGGGCACCGGCCUGGGGCACGUGACUGAGCCCUCCCCCCGCUCCCCAGGGGCUUUUGUGAGACUUUCUCGGUGAUGCUCACGGGGCGCAUGCCCACCUGGCCCGUACUAAAGCGUCAACUGUUGACUUGGGCGUAGGUGACGGCAGCCACAUUGCUAACCUUUGGGCAAGGAUUGUUUGUAAGGGAGGCGGGUGCACGGCUGGCUAGAUUUCUGGCAGGAAGCCACUGGGCGGAAGUUUGCUGAGGGUCAGGUGGUGUCAGGGCACAGGUGGCCCCUGGGGCCGCGGGGCAGUGAGCUGAGGGCCCGGCCUCUCCCUGGGUCCUCUGUCCGCUCUCAUAUCUCCCCCGUUGCUGCUGCCUUAGCCGCCUGUCACCGGCCUUCCUCCCCUUCUCCGCACGCAUCCCAGUCACAGACCCUGACCUUAGGCUGCCAGGGAAGCUAGGCUCUUAAGCACAGCCAGAAAAGGACAAAGAGGGAGGCAGGUCAGCUCCAGGAGUGAAUGGAAGCCGUACAGCUGGCCUUCCAGGGAAAGACAAGUCUGUCUGAGUGAUACCCUUUCCUUUCCUGUCUGCCCUCAAUCUUGUGGAUUACUGGAGUGGGCAAGGUCUUAGAGAAUGUCUGUCGAGGAUGUCUGCAGGUUUUAAACAGUGCCUGCCUGGCAGAGAGGGCUAGCUCUGGGCCUGGGCAGGGCAGGCCCCAUCAGCAAUCCUGCCAGAAGGACCACCUUUUCAGGGUCACCUUGGGUUCCACAGCCUUUCCAGGUGGGUAGAGGGUGGAGGGAGGUUGAGGCAGGAGGGUGCUGGGCUAGGAGUGUGCUGCCCUCGCUAGGCAUGCCCUUAUCCAGAGGCAACGGAUACGGUAGGGCAGGCCCUACCCCCAAAUCACAAAAAGGCCCCGAGUUUGUGUCACUGCUCUUCAGGGCAAGUACGCUUUUGACUUUGUAGGAGAGACUGGUGGGUUUGAAGUUAGGCAUUGGAUCCAGUCCUGUCAUGUCUGGUUAGCUGUUUUCCCUGCAGAUUAGGGUGGGCAGUGCAGUGGGGUGACAUGGUCAGUGGUGAGAAAGGAAAGGUCCUGACUAUGGCCUGUAGGCCACACCUCCUUCCUUCUUGGUCAGUGGCCCUGCCGACUCCCAGAUUUGCUGUGGAGUCUUACUCAGUUCUGUGCCUCUCAAAGUGAGGUACCUCUGCCUUUCCUGGGAGUUCCUGGGGCUCUGUUGGGUCUACAGAUGAAGCUUCAGGAGAAACUUGUGGCAUUGCCCUGAGUUGUCAGUUGCAUCUGCAGAUUUUUGGGGGCAUGGUUAUGUGAACAUCAAAAUGCUGUAUUACAGGGUAGAAUGCAAAAAUGCAGGGUGUUUUAGAGAUGCGGCAGGAGUUCAGACAAGGGUUGUGUGCCGGGCUGGUCCUUGGGUAAGGUUUUCCUCCUCCAGGGUGAGGGGAUCAGAGAGAGUACCUGGAGAGGGUCUACCCUGGGUCCUAAGAGCAUCUGGAGGUGAUACCUUGGGAGGGGACAGGAUUGCAUGGUGACAGCCCCCUCACGUGGAAGAUAUCAGCAUUGAGGCCCCCAAGUGGACAUCCUCCAGCCCUUUAUUGCUAAAGGAUUCCUGGCUGGAGCCUGCUGGUCUGGCUUGACACCUGGUCCUCCCCCAAGGCUGGCUGUGGGUUGGACAGCUGGGGUAGGGUUGGAGCUGGAGGCCAAAUGCUGACUGCAGCAGGAAGCACAGCCGAGCUGUCAGCUUGCGCGAUCUCUGGCCUCUUCAACUGCAUCACCAUCCACCCUCUGAACAUUGCGGCCGGCGUGUGGAUGAUCAUGAAUGCCUUCAUCUUGUUGCUGUGUGAGGCGCCCUUCUGCUGCCAGUUCAUCGAGUUUGCAAACACAGUGGCGGAGAAGGUGGACCGGCUGCGCUCCUGGCAGAAGGCUGUCUUCUACUGCGGGAUGGCGGUCGUUCCCAUCGUCAUCAGCCUGACCCUGACCACGCUGCUGGGCAACGCCAUCGCCUUUGCUACGGGGGUGCUGUACGGACUCUCUGCUCUGGGCAAAAAAGCCCAGACUGAGGCUGGUUCCUUCGCAGCCCAGCAUCCCAGGGAGCCUGGGCCAUUCUCAGAGGGGACAAGACAGGCCUUUGCCACCCCAGCAGUUGUCUCUGGGGAAAUCAGAAUGCCUGCAGGGGCGAUGCGAUCUCCUAUGCCAGGAUCCAGCAGCAGAGGCAGCAGGCGGAUGAGGAGAAGCUCGCGGAGACCCUGGAGGGGGAGCUGUGAAGGGCUGGGCGCCCCUCCCUCCCUGUCCCCUCUUCUGGCUCUGUGUGGGUCCAAGUGAGGCCUGGACUGUCCACGCUGAGGCACAGCCUGGAGAGGGGCCUUUGCACGUGUCCCUACACCUGGAGUCCUCUGCUCCUUUCUCCAGACUGGCUUAAGCCAGGAGCCACUGGCUGCUGGUGUGAGGGUCUGGGCUGCUGGACUUGAGGCAGAGCCUGCAGCAGCUGUGUGGACACUACCCAGCCCUACUCCUCUGCUGGGUGGGUCUGCAGAUCUCACACCACAGACAGGGCUGCCUGUGACCUGCUGUGACCUGGGAGCAGCUUCCCCUGGAGAUGCUGGUCCUGGCUUGAGGGGAGGGGCAAGUGGGACCCUGCCACCUGGGCACUGAGCAGAGGGACCUCCCCCAGCUCUCUUAGCAGGUGGAGCCCCAGGGCCUGGGACAGCCUGCCGCUGCCAGCAACCUCCCACUGCUGCCUAGGGUGCAGCGCCCACUGUCACCCUGCCUUCUGAAGAAGCCCACAGGGCUCCUAAGGUGCACCCCGGUACCUGGAACUGCAGCCUUGGCAGUGACUGGACAGCUGGGUGGGGGAUGCUCCCUGCUGGCCCUGGGAACCUUGGACAGGCCACCUCAAGGCCCCUCGGCUGCCCCUCCUCCCUGGGCCUGCUGGGGCCCCUAGGUUCUGCCCAUCACCCCCCGCCCCUGCUGGCCUUGGUGCUAAGGAAGUGGGGAGAGCAGGCUCUCCCUGGCACCGAGGGUGCCCACCCUCUCCCUGGUGUGGCCCCGUCAACAUCAGCCACAGCCCAGCCCCAUUAGUGGGUUAGUGGGUCUGACCUCAGCCCCACUCAGGUGCUCCUGCUGGCCUGCCCAAGCCCUGCCCUCAGGGAGCUUCUGCCUUUUAAGAACUGGGCAGAGGCCACAGUCACCUCCCCACACAGAGCUGUCCCCACUGCCCUGGGUGCCAGGCUGUCCGGAGCCAGGCCUACCCAGGGAGGAUGCAGAGAGCUGGUGCCCAGGAUGUGCACCCCCAUAUUCCCUCUGCCCUGUGGCCUCAGCCCGCUGGCCUCUCUGACCGUGAGGCUGGCUCUCAGCCAUCGGGCAGGUGCCUGGUCGGGCCUGGCUUAGCCCAGGUGGGGUUUGGCAGAAGCGGGCGGGUGUGGAAGAUAUUCCAUCUGGGGCCAACCCCAGGCUGGGCCUGCGCUGAGCUUCUGGAGCGCAGGUACUGGGUCUUGCUAAGUGAACUGUUUCCCAGGAACACCUCUCGGGCCCAUCUGCGUCUGAGGCUGGGAGUGGCAUCUGAGGCCGGGAGUGGCAUCUGAGGCCAGGAGUGGCAGGCUGGUGGGCUGGGCGUGGGGUUUUCUGGGCCCUGCCCAGUACUGCCCUGGGGACUUGGUGGGCUCCUGGGUCAGCAGCAUCCCACCCCUGGGAGUCUGGCCAGCUGAGCCCCAGGGUGGCAGGGGCAUUAUAGCCUGGUGGACAUGUGCCUUCAGGGUUCCUCCGGGGCCACCUUCCUCAGGCCAGUGCUGGGUUCAAAGGGCUGUGUGUGUGUGUGUGUGUGUGUGUGUGUGUGUGUGUAUGUAUAUGUGUGUGGGUGCACACAUCUGUCCCAUGUAUGCAGUGAGACCUGUCUACCUCCCACAAGGAGCAAGGGCUCUGCCCGCCCUCUGCUCAUUCCUACCCAGGUAGUGGGACCCCGGGCCCCCUUCUGCCUGGCUUGCCUGCUUCUGCCCUUUCCAGAGGGGUCUCACUGACAGCCAGAGACAGCAGGAGAAGGGUUGGCUGUGGAUCAAGGAAGGCUGCCCCUGUACCCUGUGGGGAAAUGGUGGGUGCAUGGCUGGAUGCAGAGGUGGAAGGCCCUGGGCCACAGGCGAGAGUGGGCGUGUCACCUGUCCCAGGUUCCCAGCAAGUCUGCAGCUGUGCAGUCCUGGGGUCCCUGACCCUGUCGCCCAGGGGGCGUGCUGUCCAGCAGGGGCCCUGCCUUGCAAGGAACGUCUCUUCCGGCGGCUGGGCCGCUCCUGCCUGGUCUGGGCUGUGUGUGGCGCCCUUUCCUCCUUGUUUGUUCCUCUGUGUUCUGUGUGCGUCUUAAGCAAUAAAGCGUGGCCGUGGCUCGCGUGCCUGCCCUCUGCUCCCUUCUGCCUUGGUGCCUGUGUGUGAGUGUGGAAGCCAGGCAGGAGCCGCUGGCCCAGGAAAUAACUAC